GGGAAGAUGGCGCUACGUCUGCUGCGGAGGGCGGCGCGCGGAGCUGCGGCGGCGGCGCUGCUGAGGCUGAAAGCGUCUCUAGCAGCUGAUAUCCCCAGACUUGGAUAUAGUUCCUCAUCCCAUCACAAGUACAUCCCCCGGAGGGCAGUGCUUUAUGUACCUGGAAAUGAUGAAAAGAAAAUAAAGAAGAUUCCAUCCCUGAAUGUAGAUUGUGCAGUGCUCGACUGUGAGGAUGGAGUGGCUGCAAACAAAAAGAAUGAAGCUCGACUGAGAAUUGUAAAAACUCUUGAAGACAUUGAUCUGGGCCCUACUGAAAAAUGUGUGAGAGUCAACUCAGUUUCCAGUGGUCUGGCGGAAGAAGACCUAGAGACCCUUUUGCAAUCCCGGGUCCUUCCUUCCAGCCUGAUGCUACCAAAGGUGGAAAGUCCUGAAGAAAUCCAGUGGGCAGUGUGUGAAGAAACCCUGAAGGUCGGGCCUCAAGUAGGUCUCUUUCUAGAUGCAGUCGUUUUUGGAGGAGAAGACUUUCGAGCCAGCAUAGGUGCAACAAGUAGUAAAGAAACCCUGGAUAUUCUCUACGCCCGGCAAAAGAUUGUUGUCAUAGCGAAAGCCUUUGGUCUCCAAGCCAUAGAUCUGGUGUACAUUGACUUUCGAGAUGGAGCUGGGCUGCUUAGACAGUCACGAGAAGGAGCCGCCAUGGGCUUCACUGGUAAGCAGGUGAUUCACCCUAACCAAAUUGCCGUGGUCCAGGAGCAGUUUUCUCCUUCCCCUGAAAAAAUUAAGUGGGCUGAAGAACUGAUUGCUGCCUUUAAAGAACAUCAACAAUUAGGAAAGGGGGCCUUUACUUUCCAAGGGAGUAUGAUCGACAUGCCAUUACUGAAGCAGGCCCAGAACACUGUUACGCUUGCCACCUCCAUCAAGGAAAAAUGAUCUGUUAAAUGAAGCUGUCAUCAGGGAAUGCUGAGCUGCAAUGACCAUUACUGUAGAGUUACAACAAGAGGGUAAAGUUCAUACAUGGCGACCUGUGUCAAAUCCGUCCAUUGAUCUGCCCUCCAGCACACAUUUACUGAGCUUCUGUUACGUGCCUGUGGUGAGUGACAUGACAUCACUGUGUUAGUGACUGGCCAAAAGGGUGUCUUGAAGCCGCCCUAGGGCCCUUCUGGCCCUGUUCUAGGAAGUGAAAGCUGGGGGCAGUGGAGCCCUUUCUUAUUCUGUCCACCCUCCCCCACCUCCAUUCUGUUCCAAUUAUUCUUCAUUAUCCUUCAAAGCAAACUUGCAAGUCAGCCAAGAACCGAGCUCCAGGUGUGAGACCAAAAAAAGAAAGAAAAGGGGGAAGAAAUCUAAAAGUACCUUAGAUGGAAAUUUUCAUGCAGCCAUAAAAAAGUGUUUUUUGGUUGUUGUUUUUGCUUUUUUUUUUUUAGAUCAAACAUGUUUUGUUGUUGUUGUGGUGGUGGUUGUGGUUGUUUUUGAGACAGGGUCUCUGUCUGUCGCCCAGACUGGAGUACAGCUGCACGAUCUCGGCUCACUGCAGCCUCGACCUCCCCUGCUCAAGCCAUCCUCCCACCUCAGCCAGGACCCCACCCAAGUAGCAGGAACUACAGGCCUGUGCCACCACUCCCAGAUGAUUUUUGUAUUUUUUGUAGAAACGGGGUCUCACCAUGUUGCCCAGUCUGUUCUUGAACUCCUGGGCUCAAGUGAUCCACCUGCCUCAGCCUCCCAAAGUGCUAGGAUUACAGGCAUGAGCCAUGACACUCUGCCAGAUUCAACAUGUUUAAUGGCAAAAGGGAAAAUGCUGAGAAGUUUGCCUCCAUUUGGUUAUUUCACUUUGUUCCUUUUAUACUUUCCUGUACAUUCCAAAUGGACUACAAUGAGCACCUGUCACUGUGAUCAUCAAGAAAUAAAAUAAACAAUAAAAUAAGUAAAUGUCACUACAGGGGAUUUUGGAGUUUCCCUAUUUUCUAAAAUGGACAUUUAAAAGUUUUCAAAUCAGAAAAAUGUCUGUUAAGAUUUCAUUUUAUUGUUGUUUUACAUAAGAAUAAUCAGAUAUGAGGAAAAUAAGUGUGAGUGAAAAUCAGAAUUUGAAUGGGAACUGAAGGACCCCCAGAGCUUUUUUGAGUUUUCUUUUUUUUUUCUUUUUUGAGACAAAGUCUUGCUCGGUCACCCAGUGGCGCGAUCUCGGCUCAAUACCACCUCCGCCUCCCGGGUUCAAGCAAUUCUCCUGUCUCAGCCUCCUGAGUAGCUGGGAUUACAGGUGCCUGCCACCACACCCAGCUAAUUUUUGUAUUUUUAGUAGAAAUGGGGUUUCUCCAUGUUGGCCAGGCUGGUCUCGAGCUCCUGACCUCAGGUGAUCCACCCUCCUCAGCCUCCCAAAGUGCUGGGCUUACAGGCGUGAGCCACCGUGCCCGGCCUUGAGUUCUUAUUAUUACAAGAUGACUCAGAUUUGGGCUGGAGAGCAUUUUAAAACAUUAAAACAUCUUCUGCCUAACAAAUGCAUUAAUCCUUUCUUGAGGAUUAAGAAAGAAUUAAUCCCUCCAAGGAUGGGCAGCCCCACAGCGGGUGGCUUGGAAAAUACUUGGCUUCGUGCAUCUGCAGACUUACUGUUUUCUUUGACCCUUUGCGUCUACAUCUGGGAAUUUAUCCUAAAGAAAUUCUGUAAUCCAGAAUAUCAAAAAAGCCUCAUUGGCAAAUACUACUUUAUUCACAGUUGCAUCAUGUAAAUUACAGAGGUAUGGCUAAGUCAAUCGGGAGACAUUUACUUGAUGGAAUAUUAGACAGCCACUAAAACUGGUGCUUCUGAAGGUGAUAAGAAAGUGCUUUUCCUAUAAAGUCAAGUUCUGAUGCAUACCAAGCUGCAAAUGCGAGUCUGGAGCUGAACUGCCUGGCUCUCCUGCUUCUUAGGCUUCUUAGCUAAGUAACCUUGAGCAAGAUCCUAACAUCCCUGUGCCUCAGUCUUAUUAUCUGUGAAAUGGGGGUAAUAAUACUACCUACCUCCUAAGGUUUCUUUUGAGCCUGAAAUGAGUUAAUACAUACAAAGCACAGUGGCCUGGCACACUGUAGGCACUGGACAAGUGUUGGUUCCUAUAAUUAUUAUCUGUGAUUAUAACCAUGUUAAAAAGAAAUCACAACACUGGAAAAAAAAAACAAUAAAAUGUUAGCAAUUGUAGUGUUUGGGUGAUAAGACUACUGGUGAUUUUUAUUUUUUCUUCUUUUUACAUUUUUGUAUUUCCAAAUUUUUCACUAACUAUACAUCAAUUUUUUUUAAUUGGGCAUGAUGGGUCACACCUGUAAUCCCAGAGACUCAGGAGGCUGAACCAGGAGGAUUGCCUGAGGCCAAGAGUUCAAAACCAGCCUGGCAACGUAGCAUGACCCCUCUAUCUCUAAAAAAUAAAUAAAUAAAGCUGGGCAUGGUAGUGCUUGCUUGUAGUCCCAGCUACUCAGGAGACUGAGGUGGGAGGAUCAGUUUGAGCUCAGGAGUUUGAGGCCAGCCUGGCCAGCAUAGCAAGACUCCAUCUCAAAAACAAUUAAAAAGACCCUGAAUAGAGAGCCGCAGCACGUGGUUUCAUAUGAUUUGAAACAUCCAGGUGCCAAGACUUUGGGCAUGGGCUUGCGAGGGACUCCUCCUGACUGCACCCCAUGGGCACCUCUCAUCCCGGGGAGGACGGUCAGGCUGUGCUGAGUGGUGAACAGCACUCGGAUUGGCAAAAAAGUAACCUGAGCUCCAGUCACCUGUUCCCUGCAGGUUCUUGGAAAGAGCUUUUUCCUUCUCUACAAGGAGGAAUCUGAUGCAACUGACAUCCUCAAUAGCUACAGAGAACUUGCAAAGGAGUAGAGAGAAUGUUUGAGGUCCAGCCUUGGUGUAGAGAAGCGGCAGAAACAGAAAUCCCAAAAGGUGUCAUGCUUGGCUCCAGCUCUGUGCUCUCAGAACUCCCUUCCCUCUGGGCAGAGGCCCAUCUGCUCUGUUUACACACCUGGACCUGGUGUGAAGGGAGGUUUGGAGGAGGGUAGCUCCCUGACCAUUUGUGGAAUCGUUCCUGCUUCCAAGCAGCAUGCUACAGGCCAGCCUUCAAAGAAAGACCAGAAGCCAAGUGUACUCUGUCAUCACUUAAUAAUGCUUGAAGCUUUUCAUAUAACAAAAGGAAUGAAGCAGCCCCGCCUCGCAGUGUGGAAGCCUGAUCAUUCUUCCAUCAGCUCUGCACCAAAAAGCUUUUCCUGAGCUUUGAAUAUUAGAUCUGACCAAUAUGGGUAACCAAUGCCCUUAGGUAAGGUAAAAUAGGAAUAAAAUAGCUGUUUGCAAUGUUAUUUCACCACACAGUGUGGUAGGGAGGGAACUGAUAUGUUGCAAUGCAAAGUAAUCUAGUAGUACUGUUUGUAGAACAGACAAGUGUGUCCAAUUUAAAGAAUAUCAACAUCAUUUUUCUAUAUCAUACUCUUGUGAGGUUGGAUUUAACCACAGAGGCAGAAAGUUGGUCUACUUUGCUCGUUCCUGGCAACUAGCAUGGUGCCUGCCCCUAAUACAUUUUCACUGAAUGAAUGAAUCAGUGAGUUAAUGAAUAAAUAAACAAAUGGGAGGUGUUCUCCUUUAUAUUGUGUUAGAGGCUGAGGAUAUAGAAAUAUGUAACUCAGAGUCCCAUUCCACAAGCCCAUGCUAGUGAGCCAACACAAACAAAAAACAACUCAAAUUCAAUGUGAUUAAUUCCUAAAAUCAUAGCACUAACAUUCAGUAGUCAUGUCCAGCUCUUCCUUUAUGUCAGGUACCUAGACAUAGCGGAACAGAAAACCCUUCAAAAGUUCAGUCUAGUCUGGAAAACAAACAUGAAGCAAAGAAGGCACAACACCAUAUGGAAAAGCAAGACAGAAAUAUGUACAGGGCAGAGAGGCUGCACUGUGUCAUUUAAUCACGAAGACUCUGUUAUUAGACUGCUCGAAUACACAAAGCUGUGUUACCUUGGACAUGUUACUUCACCUCUCUGGGCUUCAGUUGUCUCAUUCUGUAAAAUGGUGAUAUUACUGGAACUCAUCUCAUAGGGUUGUUAGUGAGUGAAUGUUUGUAAAACAGGAUAGUGCCCAGCACAUACUAGUAACAAAUGUAAAAUACAUGAAACAAAUAAAUAUUUCCUGUGUCCUCUGAA